GGCUUGAGAGAUCCUCCCACCUUGGCCCCCCAAAGUGCUGGGAUUAUAGGCAUGAGCCUCUGUGCCUGGCCUACUAAUCCUUUCUUUUAGGCAGGACCAGCAUGGGGUGCCCACUCCCAUUAGUGGGGCUUCCCAGCCCUGCCCCUCCCUCUGGGCAGAGACUGCGUUUAAAAUGCCCCAGCUGUCCUCACCAGGUUGCCUGGGUGCUCUGCAGGCCCCAGCCUCCCUCCUCGCCUGCUCGGGCCACCUCCACCCCGGCCUCAUGGCCACAGGGCCCCUCCCUGGUCCUGUUCUUGCUCCAGGGCCACGGCCCACGCUGCGGUUCAGGCAUGUGUGGAGCCAGGCAGGGUGGGGGUAGGGGGGCGGCUGGCAGGCCCAGGCCCUGCAGGGGGAAUGCCCGGGUUUGGCCACAGCUGGGCCCUGUCCCUUAUGGCUGCGGCAGGUCACGCUGUCUGCCUGGGACGCAACAUUCUGUGACAGGGAGGAAGGCUGGGGCAGGCUGCGUGGGGCCUCUGAACCCCCAGCAUGGGGCACUUGGAAGGGGGCUGAAGGGGGCAGGGCCUCAGAAAUGAGAAGAAGAGGUGGAAGGUGGACCUGGGGGCCCCUCCUACCCCACCUGGCUGGAACCCAAGAGACCGCAGCUGCCAGGAUGAGGCUGCUGUGUGGCCUGUGGCUGUGGCUCUCCUUGCUGAAAGUCCUGCAGGCCCAGACCCCAACCCCCCUGCCACUCCCGCCCCCGAUGCAGAGCUUCCAAGGAAACCAGUUCCAGGGGGAAUGGUUCGUCCUGGGCCUGGCGGGCAACAGCUUCAGGCCGGAGCACAGGGCGCUGCUGAACGCUUUCACCGCAACUUUUGAGCUAAGUGAUGAUGGCCGCUUUGAGGUGUGGAAUGCGAUGACUCGAGGCCAGCACUGUGACACAUGGUCUUAUGUGCUGAUACCGGCAGCCCAGCCUGGGCAGUUCACUGUGGACCACGGUGUGGAGCCCGGGGCGGACAGAGAGGAGACCCGGGUGGUGGACAGCGACUACACCCAGUUCGCCCUGAUGCUGUCCCGCAGACACACGAGCAGGCUGGCCGUCCUCAGGAUCAGCCUGCUGGGCAGGAGCUGGUUGCUGCCUCCCGGGACGCUGGACCAGUUCAUCUGCCUGGGCAGAGCUCAGGGCCUCUCGGAUGACAACAUCGUCUUCCCAGAUGUGACUGGUAACAUGGUUCACCUGCAGGCAUGCUGGGCAGUAGGCACGGGGCCCGCAGGAAUGAGUUUGGUUGACCCUAGAGGAGCUGGACCCAGUGUCUACCCAGGGAGCUCAGCCCCAGCCUGCGCUCAGGGGUCUCCAGGCUCCUGGGUCCCUGUGCUCAACCCAGGCUCUGAGCCACCUCCUGCCGCCCCGGGUCCCCUGUCCUGGGCCACCUCCUCCCACCCCGGGUCUCCUGUCCCGGGCCACCUCCUCCCGCCCCAGGUCCCCUGUCCCGGGCCACCUCCCCCUGCCCCUCCCGCCCCAGGUCCCCUGUCCCGGCCCACCUCCUCCCACCCCGGGUCUCCUGUCCUGGGCUACCUCCUCCCACCCCAGGUCCCCUGUCCCGGGCCAUCUCCUCCCUCUGGGUCCCCUGUCCUGGGCCACCUCCUCCCCUCACCCAUCCCUGCUCACAAGGAGCUUGGACUCAUCCCAGGAGGUGCCCUGGACCUCAGCAGCCUGCCCUGGGUGGCAGCCCCAGCCUGACCACUCAGACAGCCGCGGCCCCCAAGGCCUGACUCUUCUUGUGGGAGGGCGAGGUCAGCCUGAGUCCCUCCUCUUCCUGGAGGGAUGCCCACCGUGCCCUUCUGAUUCCCGCCUCUGGUCCUUUACAUGUGCAUAACCACAUGCACACACACUCACGCAUGAGCAAACGUGUACAGACUGGCACAUGCCUCCACAUGCGAACACCCACUUACACACACGCCACUCACACUGGCACACAUGCUGUCUACCCGUGCACAGGCACACGUGCUGGUCUGCACACACCUGCACACACCUGCACACUCGCUAUGCCAGGCCUCCUGGGUCUGCAGUGAGUCUGGGGGCCCAUGGGGACAGGGACAGGUGAGGGGCUUCCUGAGGACCUGGGGCUGUUGGGAGCCGCUGUGGGCCACAUCUUCUGCCCCUUCUCAGCCUCCCUCACCCCAGCCCCUUCCCCUAGACCCACUGCUGGUCCCCUUUCUCCCUCCUGCUUCUCACCUGAAGCCACCUGCCCCUCCUUUGUGCCCUCCCUUGCUUCCUCCUGGGCUCUGUCCCCUGCUCCCCCUUUGUCCUCCAUCCCGACUCCAUCUCCCCCACCAGGCUGGUCACCCCAGGCCAGCGUCUGUUGAAGGAUGAAGCAGCUCCUGUCCGGCCCAGCCCUGCCUCACAGCUGUGCGAGCUCUGCCCUCCUCAGCUCUCAAACCUGAAUAAAUGCACCAAGCCCAGAGCCCCAGAGUGUGACCACUAUGACCUUGGGUUGGGCAAAGAGACAGGAGCAAGGCGACCGCUGACCCUGCAGGGCUGCAACAGCUCCUUCUCUGGGCACACUAUGGCCCCCCAGCCGGCUGUCUCUGGCCAGUGUGUGUGACUCUGUCAGUGAGGGCAUGCACAUGUAUGUUCAUGCAUGAGUCUUUGCCCAUGGUUGCAGGUUGUACAAGGUCGUUCCCAGGCCAAGGCCCCUCCAUCCCUGCCCCUUGGGCCCUUGGCUGUGGGAGUUCGCAGGCUCUUCUCCACCUCCACCCUGGUCAGCACUCGGGGCUGCCAUACCAGAUGCAGCCGGGCUGGAGCUUGCCCCGGAAACACUCAGACCCCGAGCUGUCCCAGGCAGCGGCUGUUCUGUCAGGGAAGCUGGCCUGGAGCUACCAGGGUCCCAGAACAGGAGGAGGCCCUGGUGCAGAUGCCCCAGGCCUGGGAGAGGGGAGGCGGUGACAAGCAGCCUCGGGCUGGAGCCUGCUGGGCACAGAGACACAAAGGGUCUGAGGUCACAACCCAGACACCCACUCCCAGCCUGAGCCCCCCAACCCUGACUGUACACCCCUGCAAGAUGUCUGUAUUCGGACGCCCACCCCCACCGGCCAGCCAGAGCAACUCAUUUCUCAGCCCUCCGAUGUCUGUGUCCAUCUCAGCCCCCACUGUCCUCCGGGCAGGGAGAGCAGGACACCACCCAGGGCGGCCAUGGACCCUAGUGGUCUCUGGCCUUGCUAGAGAGUAAAGAGCAUCCAGAGACCCCCAACCUGGUGCCUAACCUUCACCCACCAGGAGCACCCCGCUACUCAGAAGCAUGGCCCUUGUUUAGAAUCCUUCUGCCAUCAUGUGCACCUCCUGCUGGGCAGGCUGUACAGGAUCCAAGCAGAUUCUGGAACUGGAAGACGGACAGAGACAGCAGACAGACUGGAAUUCCUCCCUGCCCUGACGGCCCCAACGAGAUGGAUCCCCAUGAUCAAGUCAAACGACACCAGCUGUGGUGCUUACUGCAGCCACAAUUCAA